AGAGCCCCGGAGCGCCCACCGCCGUCAGCCGCGUCUUCAAGCUAGUCGGCCCCGCGGAGAGCGAGAGACCCUGCGCACCGCAGCCCUCUCCGCUGCGCCCAUUCCUGCCGCCGGCGAUGUAACUCGGGGAGGCAGCGGUGCCCGCUGGCCCGGGGUUGAGACAGGCGGCAGGUGCCUGUGAGGCGGGCGGGUGCCGGGGGCCAGCAGGAUGGAGGAAAGCAUGGAAGAGGAGGAGGGGGGCAGCUACGAGGCGAUGAUGGACGACCAGAACCACAACAACUGGGAGGCUGCGGUGGACGGCUUCCGGCAGCCCCUGCCACCUCCGCCGCCCCCCUCGUCGAUCCCGGCCCCUGCCCGAGAGCCUCCGGGGGGGCAGCUGCUGGCGGUGCCCGCGGUCUCCGUGGACAGGAAAGGCCCCAAGGAGGGGCUCCCGAUGGGGCCGCAGCCACCGCCGGAGGCUAAUGGGGUGAUCAUGAUGUUGAAGAGCUGCGACGCGGCCGCCGCCGUGGCCAAGGCGGCCCCCGCCCCCACCGCCAGCUCCACCAUCAACAUCAACACCUCCACCUCCAAGUUCUUAAUGAAUGUUAUAACUAUUGAAGAUUAUAAGAGCACAUACUGGCCAAAAUUGGAUGGUGCCAUAGAUCAACUUUUAACUCAGAGUCCUGGUGACUAUAUCCCCAUAUCCUAUGAACAGAUAUACAGUUGUGUGUAUAAAUGUGUAUGCCAGCAGCACUCGGAACAGAUGUAUAGUGAUCUGAUUAAAAAGAUAACUAAUCACUUAGAGAGAGUCUCAAAGGAGCUGCAGGCCAGCCCUCCAGAUCUCUAUAUUGAAAGAUUUAAUAUAGCUCUUGGACAAUAUAUGGGAGCAUUGCAGAGCAUUGUGCCUCUUUUCAUAUAUAUGAAUAAGUUUUACAUCGAAACCAAGCUUAACAGAGACUUAAAAGAUGACCUUAUAAAGCUGUUUACGGAACAUGUUGCAGAAAAGCACAUUUACAGCCUAAUGCCUUUACUUUUAGAAGCCCAGUCAACACCAUUUCAGGUCACACCUUCAACUAUGGCAAAUAUUGUGAAAGGCCUGUAUACCCUCAGACCAGAGUGGGUUCAGAUGGCUCCAACUCUAUUUUCUAAAUUUAUUCCAAACAUUCUCCCUCCGGCGGUGGAAUCUGAACUUUCUGAAUAUGCUGCUCAAGAUCAGAAAUUUCAAAGAGAACUUAUACAGAAUGGUUUUACAAGGGGUGACCAGUCCCGGAAGAGAGCUGGGGAUGAGUUGGCUUAUAAUAGCUCGUCAGCAUGUGCAAGUUCCAGGGGGUACAGAUAGUGAAUGUAUUGAAUAUGCUUUCCUUCCUGAAAAGAGGACACACUGGAGCUGCAGAGACUGUAUUCAGAGCACAGUGGGGGCUGCACACACUCAGGAGCUCUGUCACAAAGCUGUUCAUGGAAGAGGAUGUUGGACUUCUUACUUGGUUUGUAAUUUUAAAACAAAAACUAAAAAAAAAAAAAACGUUGCUGCUAGACUUGGGGGUGAUUUUGAAAUGGGACAAUCUUUUAAUGAGUUUAUCUACAGAUUCUGUGAGGAAAAAGCAUCUCAGAAAGUGACCAUUUCUAAGUGAAAUCUGACAGCCAAAAUCAGCAGCUUCCUCCAAAAAUAUAAGAGCAGAAGAAUUUUUUUUUUAAGCACUUGUUUUGUUCAUUUGUGGACUUGGCAUUUUGGUGUAUUGGUUUCACAUGUCAGGAUCUCUUUUGCUUUAAAACCAAGCAGAUCAUUACAGUACAGUAUUUUUCACCCACAACCAAAACAACCCCUUUUAAAAGAGUUGGUCUUUGUUUAGCAUUAGAAAGUCUUGUUAAAGGAAAAUGCUAACUCUGCUUUUGCUAGAACUUUCCCCCAUCAGUUCACAACUUUCUUCUACUCUGUGCCUUGAGCUUUGUGCACUUUGCAACUGUGUGACCAUGUUGUCAAACUCCUCCUGGAGAAGUGUAUGGUAUCUAAACUCACCCACCAAGAUGGCAGGUGUGGCCCUGUAGCAGGAUGCUAAUUAAGUGGGAAAAUAGAAACCUUUUGCACAUGGGUCGGAUUUUCCCCUGGUUCACCAGAGCAUAUUCAUAUUAAUGUUGGGGACCAACUCUCCUAGAGCAUUUCCAUUCCCUGUGCCACUUAACACGAUGUCUGUCACCAGCUGCUAUAGUAUUGGCAGUACUCUAGUUUAGGGAUGGGCGGUACUUUAGCACGGAAGCUUCCCUUAGUAUUAUUGAGAGCUACUUCCUGCGAUGCUCUAGGAAGCAGAUACAGUUAUUAAGUCCAAAUACACAGUGGUGUGGGGUUCCUGAUCACUUCAUUUUAAAUGAAUGAGAUAAUUACUUAAAAAAAGUCUGUCAUUUGAACAUUAUAUUUGAGUGUGAUAGGGAAGAAGUAGCACUGCUGUCCUAAGGCUCCCUUCCAGCUGUGGCAAAGCUAUAUUUCUGUUUCUCCACAUCCACAGUGCUUUUUAGUCCAUCAUAAAAGUUUCUGAAGCUUAUUCUAGCUGUUGUUGAAAGCCCAAGAAAAAUAGAUGUGGCAAGAGAAAAAUACUUUUCUUCUCAAUUUUGCUUGAAUCUUAAUUGAGCAUAGGCUUCUCUACUAGGCAACAUCAGACUAAUAGUAUUUACCUCUUCAGAGAACUUGAGGGGAAAAGAAACAUCCCAGGGAUGCUGUCGCAUGUCUGCUCUGCAGGUUCUUCAUACAGCUGCCUCUGCCAAUUCAGUUUAUUUUUUGGGGGGAGUGGUGUGGGUGGGAGAGUUAGAAGUGGGAUAUUGGGAGCAAGUAAGUCACCCAAUAAUUGAAGUCCUUGAUUUGUAAAACUGUUAUACAGAGAAGUAAAGAUAAAGGUUGUCAGAUUUAUUUUUUAAAGUACUUAACCAGAGUUCGUGGAUUUUGUGGACUUUAAUUGGACUCAAUUCACUCUGUGAGCAUCCUGGAUUGCAUCGAUGAACACUGAAUUACUGUAAGAACAUAGACAGGCUCUCACUAUGACCUGGACAGUUUAAGUUGCUACACUGGUAACAUUCUAGUAUCAAGGAGAAUUCCAUUCAUCAUGACAUUCACAUUUUACUUUUCUCAAUGGAAUGCUUGCUUCAGGCUUACCAAUCACACCUAGAACUGAAGUCUGAGUGAGUGGUAUUAAUAAUUUUUCUGAAAGGAAUAAAAUUGGAAUGUUUCUAAAUGUGGAGAAAUUCUUCAGUAUCCUAAUAAUAUACCCAAAUGCUUUUUCUGGGAGAGAGCAUUCUUUUACAAAAGAACUUUCCCUAUAAAAGCAUCACAGUAUAAUGUGAAUUGGCAUUAAAAUCUUUGGAUGCUUUUGCAUUAUUAAGUUCAUGGAGAAAUAUAUUCUUUUUACUAUGUAUGUAUUAAUAAAAAGUGGGCAAAGUAAAGUUUGCAAAAUUUAGUUUCUCUAAAUUUUUGCACAGUGACUGCAGCUGGCUAUGGGUCAGCUCUUAAUACAACAAAACCUUGACUGGAAGUCACUAUAGAAAGGUUGUACAUAGUCUCCCAGUCUACAUGUCCUGGCUGUUAAUCAUCUUGGCCCCUUGAGGCACAUCACAGUUUGAAGGACCUGUUUAAGUUGAAAUAGACUUUGCUUAUUUAUUGGGAUUCUAAAAAAUUCUGAGUGAGUUUGCAGUAUGAGAGGAAAUAAGAUUUCCUCCUCCUUCCUCUCAUUUUAUAUUGACUGUUUGCCAGAAACUGUUUUCUUCUGUUUUCUUAUAUUUUGUUUUUGAGAUGGAGUCUCACUCUCUCACCCAGGCUGGAGUGCAGUGGUGCAAUCUCAGCUCACUGCAACCUCUGCCUCCUGGGUUCAAGUGAUUCUCCUGCCUCGGCCUCCUGAGUAGCUGGAAUUACAGGCACGUGCCACUACGCCCGGCUACUUUUUGUAUUUUGUUUUUAGUAGAGACGGGGUUUCACCAUGUUGGUCAGGCUGGUCUUGAACUCCUGACCUCAAGUGAUCCACCCACCUCGGCCUCCCAAAGUGCUGGGAUUAUAGGUGUGAGCCACUGCACCUGGCCUUUUUUUUUUUUUUUUUUGUAUUCUUGCCAGUACAGUAUAUGGUUUUUCUACCCCAAUUACAUACUGGGUUUUGUACCACAUCACUAAAGGCCCAAAUCAUUGAAGAUACAAAACCGUACAUGCAGGCUGGUUGUCUGGUUAGUCAAUGGCUGAUUUGCUUCAACUGUCUAGUAUGUAUGUGCAGCCUGAAACUGGCUCCUUAAAAGGAAAGCCGGGUCAGUCAUCUUGAAAAAAUGACAUGUAAAAGUAAAUCGAUAAUUGUUUUGAGAGACGGUACAUGUUUUAAAGGUUGGCCUUAAGCUUCAGUAACAUUGUCAUUUUGUGACCUUUUGUUGUCACACCUGUACCCUAACCUGACAGGAAUUAACUACUGUUUUUUUGUGGGGCAGAAAGCAAAACCUGGUGUUGUGACUUUUAUCCUAAUGGUUCUUAGGCAAGGUUAGUGAGAAGAAACACAAACCCAGAUGCAUGCAUUGUGCAUUAUUUUGUAGACAAGCUACUUUUUCUUCUGUCCCUUUAACAAAUUUGCAGCAAUUACCCUCCCUUUGGGGUCUAGAGUGAAAGCUAAUUUGUGGGUAGAUGAGAUUGCAGAAGAAUGGAUGUCCAUGGCUGUGAACACUGCACACUGCACAUCCAUCUCCAGUGCUCACACUGUGCAGCUACCACUCCCUGGCUGCGUGCCAUGCUGUCGGGUUGCAGAUUUGCACACAUAAAUUCCUCAGGAAGAGUUUGCAUGAGCAUCACCUCGCAAUAUUCUGUACUGACCAAACAAGGGAUUUGAACGUUUUUCAGCACAAAAGGAUAACUUCCGAGUGGUGGUCUGUACGCAUACUAGCAAAGGUAAUGGUGAUCUAGCAAACAAAAUUGGUUUCUGCAGUUAGAAGUGAGCAGGAGCACUUGUAUUAUAGUAUUUAAAUAAUCCUGGUUAAUCUCUUUUUAAGCCGAGUAACCCCUCCAGAUUUUGCCUUUUUAUUAUUGAGGCUGGCUUUAUUUUCUUCUACUUUUUUUCCCGUUUUAUAGCAGUUAAUUAUUUUUGUGAUUAUUAUGCAAGAAGCAUUGCCCUUGAGUUAAACUGUUAUUGUUUCAUAAGCAGCUAUUAAAAUAACUGAGCAUUGUUUUAUGAACAUACACUAAUCUGAGAUACUGAAAAGCUUUGCAACUAAAAAGCAAAACAACCUACAUUAGUCAUCUAGCCAUUGUUUGGAUGUUUUGAGUUGAUUUUUUAUGGUGCCUCUUUUAGCUUGGAAUAUUACGUUUACUUUAAUCCAAGUCUAGGCCUUUUAAAGGGUCCUUAAAAUUAAAGUUCAGAAUGUGAAUCCCUUUGACAUCUAUUACAGGUUUAUAGGACCUUUUUGGUUGUGAUUACUGUUUUCAAUACGAUUGUAUAAAUGAAGUUAACUUUGUCAGAAGUUAAAAUGGAGGUCAUAGGAGUUCCUGGAGAAAUGGCUCUCCUGUUUCUUUCAUUACCCCACUGAAGUUCACCCCAGUUUCUGGCCACAAGAAUAUGAGAAAGGAACCCUGUUGUUUUCCAAGGGAAAUCAUUCCUCUCUGUCCCCACUGUUGAUUAACUAAAGUCCUGGACACCUUCCUUCCUCCACUGGCCAAGACCCACCUUGACCCACCUUGAACCUCUUUUCAGAGCCGAGUGGCAUGAAUAUGUGUACUGUUUCUGCUUCUGUUGAUGGAGUGGCUGUGGGAGAAUUAAAGGAAAUGCUAAUUUGAGCUUCAUUCAUAGGGGAACCUACUAUAUAUUGCAUCCCUGCUGGUUGGAAAUUAUCUUCAUCUCUGGACUGCAUUGUUUAGAAAAAUGUUAAUGGCUUACAAUUCUGAGAACUUUAUUGUGUGGCUCUGGGGUUAAGAAUUCUGUGGUUUGAAAAAAAAUAAAUAUUUUGUAUUGAUUCUCACGUCAUUUCAAUGUUGUGACUAUGUACUAAAUGCACUAAGACUGGGUAUUCUCUUAGAAGAGUGCGUUUUGUUAAACAGAUGGCAGUUCACUCUCAUUAGUUCUAUUUGUCAAUAUUACAGCCACACACUUCAGGAUAACUUACUCAAAUGUGAAGUCAUGGGAAGCUAUGGCUAGUAACAGGAAUGCUUAUGAAAAAUUUGGAGGGCAAGCACGAGCAAGAGGCUUUUGCCACUCACUAGCACAGCCAGAGCAAGGAUGAAGCAAUGAAGUCUUGUUCCUAGUGGUGCUUGUAUGUCAGAAGCCAUAGUGAGCUCAGCACAGGGCGUUCUGCACAUCAUCUCUUUAAUCCAAGAAAAACAAAAUGGCGGAUGAAACUCCUAUUGACCUGGGAUACAAAGCCACUGACUUUGGCUCUUGAUCUUUUGGUGGGUUCUGAAUCACUCCUUCUGUAUUAGGGCAUAUACUUUCACUCUAAAACAUUGUGGUAAAUGAAAUAAAUCUUGUACAGAUGUCGUUGGCCUUGUUAUGUUAUGUUAUAAAUCCUGUACAGAUGUCCUUGGCCUUAAUACCUGGUUCACUGGAACUUUGUUAUAAUAUAGAAUAUUUGAUUUUGCUUAUAGCAUAUUAAUAUUGCCUCCUACAUGACAGCCACACUGAGCACACAUCUGUUACCACAGUUACUUAGCCUGCAGGGUGAGUGUUGAUCUUGACUUCUGCAACCAGUGCUAAAAAACAGUGUGUAACAAUAUACAUAUGGUCAUAUCUAUUCUAUAUUCAUAUAUAGUAUGGAUACGGAUAUCAGUAUAUUUGUAGUUUUUGUUUUUUAAACACUGUACAGUUUCUUCUGUGGACCUUUAAUCAACUUUUGGACUUAGGUUGUUUUUUUCUUUGCAUUUAUUGGUACUAUGCUUUUUUAUAACCCUUUGUGUUUUCUUGCUAUGAAAUUAGUGUCAUCCCCUAGGUUAUUUGUAACCUUACUUUAAGGUUUUAGUUUCUCUUGCUAUCUCUGUAGAGGUGUCCUUUCCUACAGUAUUGUCAGAAUGCCAGUUCUCAUCCCUUCCAUUUUUUUGACCUCAGCUCUGUUGUGAUGUUAUCUACUUUUUGGUUAUCACAUGUGGCAGAAUUCAGUGACUCUGACAAUUUCCAUUUUCACUCCCCUGCCCCACAGUUAAGUAGGGUGUCAUUUAAACUCUUUCCCUUUUAGCAGGUUUGUUUUUUACUAAGUACAAACCUUUUCUACUAGAACCAGCUCUGUGUGUGUGUGUGUAUAUGUGUGAAUUUUAUUUCUUCGAUUGGCCUGUUUCUCAAUUAUCUAAAAUUCUAAAAUACCUUGAAUAUCAAAAAGCAUGAUAGUAGAAUGAAUAUCACACAUAUUAAUAGAACCUGAGAGCAACUAGCUUAACUAGCUGUAGUCUUGAGUAGGUUUUUUUUUUAAUCUGUUUUCCUUUAUUAAGCCCUCUCCCUCCCUAAAUUGUUAAGCCAGAAGGGCAUAACAAUUCAAAACUUUCUAGUAAUGUACCUACAUGUCUAAUAGUAUACCUCAAAAUAUGUAAAGAAAAAGUGGCUCACACCUGUAAUCCCAACACUGAGAGGCUGAGGUGGGAAGAUUGCUUGAAGCCAGGAUUUGAGACCAGCCUGGGUAACACAGAACCCCAUCUCUACAAAAAAAUUUUUUAAAUUAGGGCCGAGCAUGGUGGCUCACGCCUGUAAUCCCAGCCCUUUGGGAGGCUGAGGUGGGCGUAUCAUUUGAGGUCAGGAGUUCAAGACCAGCCUGGCCAACAUGGUGAAAUUCCAUCUCUACUGAAAAUACAAAAAUUAGCUGGGCGUGGGGGUACACGACUGUAAUCCCAGCUACUCGGGAGGCUGAGGCAGGAAAAUCGCCUGAACCCAGGAGGCAGAGGUUUCAGUGAACCAAGAUUGCACUAUUGUACUCCAGCCUGGGCGACAAGAGUGAAACUAUCUCAAGCAAAAAACAAAAAAAGUUGGGCCUGGCACAGUGGCUCUUGCCUGUAAUGUCAAUACUUUGGGAGGCUGAGGCAGGUGGAUCACUUGAGGCCAGGAGCUCGAGACCAGCCUGGCUAACAUGGUGAAACCCUGUCUCUACAAAAAAUAAAAAAUAAAAAUAAAUUAAAAAAAAAUUAGGCAUGGUGGCAUACACCUGUAAUCCCAGCUGCUUGGGUGGCUCAGGCACAAGAACUUGAACCCAGGAAGUGGAGGUUACAGUGGGCUAAGGUCACACCACUGGACUCUGGCCUGAGCAACAGAGCGAGACUCUGUCUCAAAAAAACACAAAAAAAGUUGGGCGUGGUGGUACCUGCUUUUAGUCCUAGUUAUUUGGAGGCUAAGGUGUGAGGCAGGAGGAUUGCUUGAGCCCAGGAGUUUGAGGCUGCAUUGAGCUAUGAUGAUACCACUGCAUUUCAGCUAGGAUAACAGAGUGAGACCCUGUCGAGAAAAAUAUUUAAAAAGUUAAAAGAAAACUACAAAAAGGAAAAAUGAACACACUACAAAGAGAAAUAGGUCAGUCUACCAACAUAAUGGGCAUUUUCAACAUACCCCUCUCAGUAAUUAAUAGAUCUUGCAGAGACUAAAUUAUGAAGAUUAUUAAGGACAUAGAAGAUUUAAAUAGUACAGCUAAUCAAUUUGAUCUGACAGAUACAUAACACACACAUACAUAAAACACAUUGUACCCUUCAGUAGGAAAAUAAGUUUUUGCAAACCAAGUCUAACAGUGUAUUCAAAAUGUAACAAAUGAUGACCAAAAUGGAUUGGUCUCAGGAAUACAAGAUUGGCUUUUUAAUGUAAUUAAGAAAUGCUGUUUAUAAUAGGACAAGAAAAAGUACCUAAGAAUAAAUUUUAAAAUGAGAAAAUGAUAAAAAAAAAACUUAAUGGACCUAAAUAAGUGUAGAGAAUAUAAGGGAUAACACUCAAUAUUAUCUAAAUCUCAACUUUUUCUCCAAAUUGCAAUUCCAAAAAAAUUCCCAAUGAUUUUCACUGUGGAACCUGACAAUUUGAUUCGUCGAUAUAAAUGGAAGAGCAAAGGGCCAAGGAUAUCCAAGACCUUUCUGAAUGGAUUGUGAGGGGAACUAGCACUACAAGAUUCUAACACUUACUGCCAAAGGUAGUGAUUAAAACAAUGACUUUGGAGUAGGGAAGAAUUUCAUCAACAAGAUAGAAAAUGCAGACUAUCAGUAGAUAAGUAAUUUGGCUACCAUUGAUUGUAAGUACUUAUUACCAAACAUGCUGUAGAGUGAAAAGAGAAGCCAAAUCUGGAAUAAGAUACAAAUAUUCAUAAUAUAACUGCUAAAGAGCACCUGAAUGCAAAUCAGCAAUGAAAACAACUCAGGAGAGACGGACCCCAAACACUAGCAGGCAUUUCACAGAAGAAACAGAAAUGGCCCAUAAAUGUGAAAAGAUGUUCAGCCUCAUUAGUCGUCAGGUAAUGCACAUUAAAAGCAUAGAUACCAUUUCCUUGCUGACAACUUGGCAGAAAUUAUGAGAAGUCUGAAAAUAACAAUCUGAGAGUUUAUGACAACAAACCUUCACCUGUUGUUGGCGUGUAAAUCUGCACUUCUACUUUGGAGAACAGUAUUAUCUAAUGAAAUUGAGCAUAGGCACCUCUUAAUAGCCCACUAUUUAUACUUAGAAAAACUCAUGUGCAUGUGUACCAAGAAACGUAUACAGGGAUGUUUAUAACAGCAUUAUGUGUAAUAAUUAAAAGGAAUGAAGGAGGGAGCCAAAUGCCCAUCUAGCAUACAGUGAAUAAAUGAAGUGUAUGCUGUGGAAUUCUCUAGAGUGGUCAAGGCAUCAUACCACUGCGGGCUUCAACAUGGAUGCAUCUCAGAAAUCAUUGAGUGAAGUCAGAAUAGAGCCAGCAUGGGUACCUUUAUGUAAAGUUCAAAAUCAGAAAAAACUAAGUAUAUUGUUUAGGGACUCAGACACAAGUAGUAAAGCUAUAAAGGAAAGACAGUUAUUAACAUUCAGGAACAUAGUUUCCUCAGGAGAGGGUGGUGGAGGGGAAUGAGAACAGAGGGGAGAACGGGGACUUGGAAGCACUUCAUAAUAUGAACGUUUGGACCAUUCUAAACAUGCCAGUUCUCUGAGUUAAUGUAUAUUCAGUGUAAAGCCAAUUCAGAUAACCAACAGUAUUUAUAUAAUCUAAAAAACUCAUGGAAGUAUAAACAGAUGAAAAUAGGAAAAUCCCCAUUGAAAGUGAAGAAAAUGGAAGGAACUUGCUGUACCAAAAAAAAUCACUUUCUAAGUGCAAUUAAAUUAAAAGACUUAUGCCAGGGUAAACAGAUAAGUCAAUGGAAGGUAAUUUAGAAAAUAGAAAACUCAAAUUUAGAAUUUAGAGUACACUAAAGGCGGCUUUUUGAAAUCAUGCUGUCCAUGGUCAAUUAUUUUAUGAAAGGUGCUGGUAUAAUUAGAGAACAUUAAACUGAUUCCUAUCAUACCAUUCACCAAGAGAAAUUCCAGAUUGUGAACUAAAAAAGAAAAAAAUGUUGUAAAAACUAGAAAGUAGUAUUUUUUCUUGGGAUUGGAGAAGUUUUUUCUAAGAAUACAAGCAAUGAAACCGAAAACCCUAUUAAACUCACUCACCUGCCUUUAAUGCCGUAGUGUGCACACCCCAGUGUGUGUGUGUGUGUGUGUGUGUGUGUGUGUGUACAUAGACAUAUAUAUUUUAAAAUGUUUAAAUUUGAACAUAUGUUACCAAUACAUAUAAAGCAAAAGUAGAAAAUCAAAAAGAUGAAGUAAAAAUGUUUUAAAAUAUUGUUUGUGGUAUUUGUGGUUAAUAAACCUUUGCUCUUUCUAAAAAAAUGUUCUUUUAGAGAGAGUCAUGAUUAAAAAUGCUUGUCAUUUUUGAAACUCCUAGUUUUAACACUUUAUAAAAACAACUUAAUGUUCUUAAGGUAAGUUUAUUUUCAUGCUUGGUUUUAAUGACUAUUGUAGCUGAAUAAGUCACUUCAUUAAUUAAGAUCUGUGGAUCCAAAUAUGGCUGUGCUUACUGAAAAUAUUUUUGAGUUCCAUCCACCAAUUUUGCAAAAGUGUGUUGUUGAAAUUUUUAUAAUAAAUUUUCAUCUUUUCCAAUGUCA